ACUGUCCCGAAGGAGGCGGCGGCGCCCACGCGGGGCUGGAGGAGCGGGGGUAGCCCGGGGCGAGGCGGCGGUUGCGGCGGCGGCUGCGCGCUCCCCGGCCUGCCGGCAGGAACCUUGGAAAAAACCCGGCUGAGUUCUGCAGAGCUGGCGGGGCCGGGCCCAGAGCUCCCCUGUGCCCAGAGCCCGGCCCGCCCUGCGGAUGAUGCCAACCUGACCAGAACCCCGCUGUCCCGGGGGCGCAGCAACUUGGUGAAGGGGACAGGGCUCCGGACUAGACAGCACCCAAGCUGGCCGCUCCCUCCCAAAGUCUGUCUUUCGGAGUGCUGGUCCCUGGCUCAGUGGCAAGGAAGACUUCAGGCCAGCAGAUCGAACCAGUGGGCAUCACCGUGGACCAGGUGGAGUGAGUCUGAGGACAGCAGAUGAACAGACAGAAACUGAAAGAUCCCCAAAAAGGAUGAGUGAGAGGGUCGAGCGGAACUGGAGCACGGGCGGCUGGCUGCUGGCACUGUGCCUGGCCUGGCUGUGGACCCACCUGACCUUGGCUGCCUUGCAGCCUCCCACUGCCACAGUGCUUGUGCAGCAGGGCACCUGCGAGGUGAUUGCGGCUCACCGCUGCUGCAACCGGAACCGCAUCGAGGAGCGCUCCCAGACGGUGAAAUGCUCCUGUUUUUCUGGCCAGGUGGCCGGCACCACGCGGGCAAAGCCCUCCUGCGUGGACGACCUGCUCUUGGCUGCCCACUGUGCUCGUAGAGACCCUAGAGCUGCACUCCGCCUCCUGCUCCCACAGCCUCCAUCGUCCUGCAGAGAUGGUGGUGUCAGAUGGAGCCCUGCCUGCCGGGGGAGGAGUGUAAGGUGCUCCCGGACCUGUCGGGAUGGAGCUGCAGCAGUGGACACAAAGUCAAAACCACCAAGGUCACACGAUAGCUCUUGGGGGUCACGGCCUGGACAAGAAAGGCUUGACUGAGCCGUGAACUGAAGAAUGGUAUCCAGUCAUCAGCCAGGAAAGAUGGGGAUUCACUUACAUGCCUCAUGUCAAAUGCAGCAUCAGUCUUUCCGGGGCAUUUCAGUUAAGCUGCUCAGCAGAUAUGGAUGGAUCUGCAAUCACAUACCUAAUGUGGAGCUGGGCUUUUCUGGAGACACGAAGGUCAACACACAAUUCCUGCCCUUAAGGAAUGUCCAGUUGAAUUGGAGAGUUGAUGACAGACAAUUUAGAUAAUUUAGGUUAAAGUACUUGAUACCAGACUGCGGCUUCUGGGCCACAUGCUAUGGCAUGAUGGGGGUUUGGGAAUGAGAUUCCCACAGUUCUUCAGAUACCCUGUGGCCACAGGGCAUAGAAACAAGAGGUCACAUUCAGCACCCACCACCUCCCUCUUUCGCAUCAGUUCUGAAUCCCCAGCAAGCUGUUAACAUGUUGCAGGAAAACACUCUCCCCUUAUGCCAGACCAGCAGUAUCUCAUUUGGAUGGGAUUGGAUUGACUUGCGGAAGGAAAGUAAAAAUAAAGCCAAAUAACUUCCCAAA